CUACUACCGGCCUCCCCUGGCUGUUAAAAGCAGAUGGUGGCUGAGGUUUGUUCAAUGCCCGCUGCCUCUGCUGUGAAGAAGCCAUUUGAUCUCAGGAGCAAGAUGGGCAAGUGGUGCCACCACCGCUUCCCCUGCUGCAGGGGGAGCGGCACGAGCAAUGUGGGCACUUCUGGAGACCAUGACGACUCCUUUAUGAAGACACUCAGGAGCAAGAUGGGCAAGUGGUGCUGUCACUGCUUCCCCUGCUGCAGGGGGAGCGGCAAGAGCAACGUGGGCACUUGGGGAGACUACGACGACAGCGCCUUCAUGGAGCCGAGGUACCACGUCCGUCGAGAAGAUCUGGACAAGCUCCACAGAGCUGCCUGGUGGGGUAAAGUCCCCAGAAAGGAUCUCAUCGUCAUGCUCAGGGACACUGACAUGAACAAGAGGGACAAGCAAAAGAGGACUGCUCUACAUUUGGCCUCUGCCAAUGGAAAUUCAGAAGUAGUACAACUCCUGCUGGACAGACGAUGUCAACUUAACGUCCUUGACAACAAAAAAAGGACAGCUCUGAUAAAGGCCGUACAAUGCCAGGAAGAUGAAUGUGUGUUAAUGUUGCUGGAACAUGGCGCUGAUGGAAAUAUUCAAGAUGAGUAUGGAAAUACCGCUCUACACUAUGCUAUCUACAAUGAAGAUAAAUUAAUGGCCAAAGCACUGCUCUUAUAUGGUGCUGAUAUUGAAUCAAAAAACAAGUGUGGCCUCACACCACUUUUGCUUGGCGUACAUGAACAAAAACAGGAAGUGGUGAAAUUUUUAAUCAAGAAAAAAGCUAAUUUAAAUGCACUUGAUAGAUAUGGAAGAACUGCCCUCAUACUUGCUGUAUGUUGUGGAUCAGCAAGUAUAGUCAAUCUUCUACUUGAGCAAAAUGUUGAUGUAUCUUCUCAAGAUCUAUCUGGACAGACAGCCAGAGAGUAUGCUGUUUCUAGUCAUCAUCAUGUAAUUUGUGAAUUACUUUCUGACUAUAAAGAAAAACAGAUGCUAAAAAUCUCUUCUGAAAACAGCAAUCCAGAACAAGACUUAAAGCUGACAUCAGAGGAAGAGUCACAAAGGCUUAAAGUCAGUGAAAAUAGCCAGCCAGAGAAAAUGUCUCAAGAACCAGAAAUAAAUAAGGACUGUGAUAGAGAGGUUGAAGAAGAAAUAAAGAAGCAUGGAAGUAAUCCUGUGGGAUUACCAGAAAACCUGACUAAUGGUGCCAGUGCUGGCAAUGGUGAUGAUGGAUUAAUUCCACAAAGGAAGAGCAGAAAACCUGAAAAUCAGCAAUUUCCUGACACUGAGAAUGAAGAGUAUCACAGUGACGAACAAAAUGAUACCCAGAAACAACUUUCUGAAGAACAGAACACUGGAAUAUCACAAGAUGAGAUUCUGACUAAUAAACAAAAGCAGAUAGAAGUGGCUGAAAAGGAAAUGAAUUCUGAGCUUUCUCUUAGUCAUAAGAAAGAAGAAGAUCUCUUGCGUGAAAACAGCAUGUUGCGGGAAGAAAUUGCCAAGCUAAGACUGGAACUAGAUGAAACAAAACAUCAGAACCAGCUAAGGGAAAAUAAAAUUUUGGAGGAAAUUGAAAGUGUAAAAGAAAAACUUCUAAAGACUAUACAACUGAAUGAAGAAGCAUUAACGAAAACCAGUAUUUAAGUACAGUGGACAGCUUAGG